GGCGGCGCCAGCGGACACCGGAGCGGGCAGGAGCAGCGGCCGCGGCGCCGCAGGGACCAGCGGGCCCAGGAUCUGCUGUGCUGUGUGACCUCCUCAGGCUGCUGGACCUCUCUGAGCCCAAGAAGGAAGAGAGGGGCUAAGAGGUGCCCCUCCCAGGAAGUGCUAUUCUAAGGAUCCUUCAGACCUGAACGGGAGGGGCUAGGGCACACCAGGCCAUAGUUUGAUUUUAGAGUUUAGGGAGUGGCGAUUUUCCCGUUCAGCUUCUGGAUUUUGUAUUUUUGUGUCCCACCUGGGCUGCAAGACCCUUCCUCCCUGGGGCGGCUAUUGGGAAUCAGUGCCCUGAUUUGCAAAUUGUGGUUCUCAGAUUCCCAGCCUCAGGAUCCCAUUUAUGGCAGGUGAGGAGAGCAGCCCUGUAAUACAAGUUCCAGCUGGAUGCGGUGUCUCACACCUGGAAUCCCAGCACUUUGGGAGCCCGAGGCGAGAGGAGCACCUGAGGUCAGGAGUUCAAGACCAGCCUGGCCAACAUGGCGAAACCCCGUCUCUACUGAAAAUACAAAAAUUAGCCGGGUGUGGUGGUGCAUGCCUGUAAUCCCAGCUACUCUGGAGGCUGAGGCAGGAGAAUUGCUUGAACCGAGGAGGCAGAGGUUGCAGUGAGCCGAGAUUGCACCACUGAACUCCAACCUGGGCAACAGAGCAAGACUUGGUUUUAAAAAAAAUAAGAAGGCCAGGUGCAGUGGCUCACGCCUGUAACCCCAGCACUUUGGGAGGCCGAGGUGGGUGGAUCACCUGAGGUCAGGAGUUCAAGACCUGCCUGACCAACAUGGAGAAACCCUGCCUCUACUAAAAAUAUAAAAUUAGCCGGGCUUUGUGGUGCAUGCCUGUAAUCCUAGCUACUUGGGAGGCUGAGGCAAGAGAAUAGCUUGAACCCGGGAGGUGGAGGUUGCGGCGAGCCAAGAUUGUGCCAUUGCACUCCAGCCUGGGCAGCAAGAGCGAAACUCUGUCUAAAAAUAAAUAAAUAAAUAAGAAGAAUAAAAUAAAAUACGAGUUCCCAGGGCCGUUGCCCUGGCCGACCGAUUCAUCACACCUAGGGCUGCGGCCCUGACAUAUGCAUCUUAAACACCCGACCAUGUGCGGCUUCCAUGAGGAUUGGCCAUCUCUGGGUUGGCGGAAGAGCAGGGGACCCAUGGUUGUUGGAGACGGGCACCGUUUGAGCCACCAAACAGGCUCAGGGUGGCAUGAUGGCUCGGCAAGGUCUCAGAGCCAGGCAGGCUCGGUCUGGGGUUCUUGCAGCUGGCACCAGCCCUCCCGGCCCCGGCCGCCCACCCGCCGCGGGGAAGAUGCCGGAACAGAGUAACGAUUACCGCGUGGUGGUGUUCGGGGCGGGCGGCGUGGGCAAGAGCUCGCUGGUGCUGCGCUUCGUGAAGGGCACGUUCCGCGACACCUACAUCCCCACCAUCGAGGACACCUACCGGCAGGUGAUCAGCUGCGACAAGAGCGUGUGCACGCUGCAGAUCACAGACACCACCGGCAGCCACCAGUUCCCGGCCAUGCAGCGCCUGUCCAUCUCCAAGGGCCACGCCUUCAUCCUGGUGUUCUCCGUCACCAGCAAGCAGUCGCUGGAGGAGCUGGGGCCCAUCUACAAGCUCAUCGUGCAGAUCAAGGGCAGCGUGGAGGACAUCCCCGUGAUGCUCGUGGGCAACAAGUGCGAUGAGACGCAGCGGGAGGUGGACACGCGCGAGGCGCAGGCGGUGGCCCAGGAGUGGAAGUGCGCUUUCAUGGAGACCUCGGCCAAGAUGAACUACAACGUCAAGGAGCUCUUCCAGGAGCUGCUGACGCUGGAGACGCGCCGGAACAUGAGCCUCAACAUCGACGGCAAGCGCUCCGGGAAGCAGAAGAGGACAGACCGCGUCAAGGGCAAAUGCACCCUCAUGUGAGCCCGGAACGCCCGCCUGCCCGCCGCCCACCCCCACUGACCCCCGCUGCCUCCCCCAACACCGACACCCUCCUCGGCCUCCUCCUCUUCUCUCAUCCUUCCUCCGACACCUCGGCUGGGGAAACCGAGGCCACCGCCCCCCCCUCCGCUGCCCCUGCCCACCCCGAGGCAGGGCUGGGGCUUUUCUUCCUCCCCUGCUCUCUCUCCACCCUCCUGUUCUGUCUGUACCCUCCAAAACCAAGAGCCGGAGGUGGCCCCCUUGUCCUGCAGAUGGGAAAACAGGAUGGGGAGCUGGCAAGAGGAGCUGCUUGUUCCCACCAGGACCAGAGGAGGCUGCGUUUCCCCGUUUCCAUCUCUUUCCCUGGGGUGUCCCCAGCCAGACCUGCGCGUCCUGUCCCUCACAUUUGAUCACUGUGACCUUCUGGGGGAGGGGGGAGUUGAAAAUGCACAUCGGCCUCAGAUAUUUUUUUCUUUUUUCUCCUAUUUGGUGUUAACAUACACCCAAGCCCACCCGGCCCGUCGUGACCUCUGAUCUGUGCCCACUCCUCCGGUUCCAGACGCACCUCUCUCCUCUGUCUUCACAGUGGGGUGUGGGGCCCGUGGGAUGGGCCUCAGGCCACCAGGCAAUAACCACAGGGCCUGCAGCAGUGCCCCUGCCAGCCCCGAAUCCCACCCCCGGGACCAGCCACAUCCACAGCACAACUGCCCCGCUGGAGAGGCACCAUGGGCGUGGAGGGGCUUCCCGGACACCGCCCACCCGGGACCCGCCUCUUCCACCAAGACAGAGACGUUAGCAACGCAUGGCGGGUGGGGACCUGGGGUGCUCAGGAGGGGGUACCCGGGGCCCCGGCCAGAGAUACAUCAAUUACACCCCCGUGGGGGGACAGCCGAUGGGAGCCAGCACCAGCAGGAUCCGAGGGCGCCCCGGACAGAGGUCUGCCCCACCCACUUCCUCCCCACCACCUGUGCCCCAGAGAGCAGGGCCUGCCCGGGAAGGUGGCGUCCUGGAGUCGAGUGUACCUGCAGCCAUGAGGUUCUGGGUGUUUUUUGAGAGAGUCUGAGUGACACCACACUCGUGUGACCCCACAGGGUUGUGUCCAACAUACACGGAAGUGGCUAUGGAAUGGUGUAUUUGUGCAACCUGGGGUGCGCGGAUGGGUGACUUGUAUCUAAGUGCAUCUGCGUGUAUACCUGUGUGUGUCUGUCUGGGAUGAUAUGUUUUUGUGGCAGUCUGUGUGUGUAAUAGUGGUGUAGGGUAUACAGAGAGGUGGGUAGUUGUAGAUACCUGUGUGUGGUUGUCAGCAAGACUGGAUAUGUGUGAGGUGUCUGUGUGAAUCUUUGUGCCUGUAUGAGCAUGACUAUAUUUUGGGGAGUGGGUGAUAUGGUUUAUCUGAGAGCAUUUAUCUGUAAAUAUGUUUGUCCUGAUUGAGGGACACGAUCUGUGUUCCACUCUAUAGCAACAUGACUCUAGCAAUGUGACUUUCGGUUCCAAAUCUGUAUCAGUCAGCUACUGCUGUGUAACAAAUGACCACAAAUGUAGCAACCAGAAACAACACAUGCUUAUUAUCUCAUAGAUUCUGUGGGUCAAGAGCCUGGGUGCAGGUUGGCUGGGUCCUCUACUUGGGAUCUCAGGAGGCUGCAAUCAAAGCAUUCGCCAGGCAGAGGUCUCAUCUGAAGGCCUGAUCGGGGAAGGAUUUGCUUCUUAGAAGCUCAUGUGGUUGUUGCAGCAUUCAGUUCCUUGCUGUUGCAAGACUGAAGGCCUCAGUUCCUCGCUGGCUGUUGGCUGGAAGCUGCCCUUUGUUCUGUACCAUGUGGGUCUCUCCACAGCGGGGCUCGGAGCAUGGCAGCUAAGUUAGUGAGGGAAGGUGAGAUGGAGGUUUUGGUCUUAUUGGGUGUGAGGAAGCAACGUGUGUGUGUGCGCACGCCCUUUUGUGCAGUGAGAGAGAGAGAGAGAUUGCACACAUGUGUCUCUGUAGUCAUGUGGCCAGGUGGGACUAUGUAGGUAACAGAUUGCUCGUGUCUGAUUUGGUACAAGCAUGUUUGUUUUCCUCUGUGUUCGUGUGAGUGUUUACUCAACAAAUGUUUAUUGGACACACUCAGAGAGAGGGAGUGUGCACACGUGCGUGUGUGUUGCUAUCCAGCACGUGGACCGGGCUCCCAGAAGAGCUGGCAUUGUGUCUGAGCAGAGCUGGGUCCCCCCAAAACUUGGGCUGGCCCAGGGCCCACCAGCAGCUGAUGUUGCCUCCUCUCCUGUCCUGGCAGUAGCUUCUGGGUUCUGAAGGUGCCGGAGAGAGUGAGGCUGGGCAGGGGUCUGCGGCCCUUUCUCAGGGACACACCCUGAUAGCACAAUCUCCUUGGGGCCCUGCCCACCUCCAGGCCUCUCCCACCUCAGGCCCUGCCCGACCCUGGGGAGAGAGGGCAUCUGCAAUAGGAGGGGACCCGAGCCUGUCCUGGCUGCUGGCCCAUCCUGCCUGGGCAUCCCUGGUGCUGGGGACUGUGCCAGGCCAUGCUUGCUGUGACUCCGCCCCUGCCCCCUCUCCCCCCGCAUGUGGGUGCCCCCACUCCCCCAUCGUGGGGUCUGUGUAGCCUUCGCUCUAGACAUAGUCUUCCUGCAAUAAAAAAGUGGAUCCUGCAUUCCCCACCA